AGGUGACUGCGCGGCGGGCUGUGGCUGCGGAGGUUGAGGGGCGUCCGAGGCGCGGAGGGGCUGGCUGGGCAGGAGGGGUUGGCGGGGCAGCAGGGCCGCGGCCAUGGGGAGCUUGAAGGAGGAGCUGCUCAAAGCCAUCUGGCACGCCUUCACCGCACUCGACCAGGACCACAGCGGCAAGGUCUCCAAGUCCCAGCUCAAGGUCCUUUCCCAUAACCUGUGCACGGUGCUGAAGGUUCCUCAUGACCCAGUUGCCCUUGAAGAGCACUUCAGGGAUGAUGAUGAGGGUCCAGUGUCCAACCAGGGCUACAUGCCUUAUUUAAACAGGUUCAUUUUGGAAAAGGUCCAAGACAACUUUGACAAGAUUGAAUUCAAUAGGAUGUGUUGGACCCUCUGUGUCAAAAAAAACCUCACAAAGAAUCCCCUGCUCAUUACAGAAGAAGAUGCAUUUAAAAUAUGGGUUAUUUUCAACUUUUUAUCUGAGGACAAGUAUCCAUUAAUUAUUGUGUCAGAAGAGAUUGAAUACCUGCUUAAGAAGCUUACAGAAGCUAUGGGAGGAGGUUGGCAGCAAGAACAAUUUGAACAUUAUAAAAUCAACUUUGAUGACAGUAAAAAUGGCCUUUCUGCAUGGGAACUUAUUGAGCUUAUUGGAAAUGGACAGUUUAGCAAAGGCAUGGACCGGCAGACUGUGUCUAUGGCAAUUAAUGAAGUCUUUAAUGAACUUAUAUUAGAUGUGUUAAAGCAGGGUUACAUGAUGAAAAAGGGCCACAGACGGAAAAACUGGACUGAAAGAUGGUUUGUACUAAAACCCAACAUAAUUUCUUACUAUGUGAGUGAGGAUCUGAAGGAUAAGAAAGGAGACAUUCUCUUGGAUGAAAAUUGCUGUGUAGAGUCCUUGCCUGACAAAGAUGGAAAGAAAUGCCUUUUUCUCGUAAAAUGUUUUGAUAAGACUUUUGAAAUCAGUGCUUCAGAUAAGAAGAAGAAACAGGAGUGGAUUCAAGCCAUUCAUUCUACUAUUCAUCUGUUGAAGCUGGGCAGCCCUCCACCACACAAAGAAGCCCGCCAGCGUCGGAAAGAACUCCGGAAGAAGCAGCUGGCUGAACAAGAGGAACUGGAGCGACAAAUGAAGGAACUCCAGGCCGCCAACGAAAGCAAGCAGCAGGAGCUGGAGGCCGUGCGGAAGAAACUGGAGGAAGCAGCAUCUCGUGCAGCAGAAGAGGAAAAGAAACGCCUUCAGACUCAAGUGGAACUUCAGGCCAGGUUCAGCACAGAGCUGGAAAGAGAGAAGCUUAUCAGACAGCAGAUGGAAGAACAGGUUGCUCAAAAGUCCUCUGAACUGGAACAGUAUUUACAGCGAGUACGGGAGCUGGAAGACAUGUACCUAAAGCUGCAGGAGGCUCUUGAAGAUGAGAGACAGGCCCGGCAAGAUGAAGAGACAGUGCGGAAGCUUCAGGCCAGGUUGUUGGAGGAAGAGUCUUCCAAGAGGGCUGAACUAGAAAAGUGGCACUUGGAGCAGCAGCAGGCCAUUCAGACAACCGAGGCGGAGAAGCAGGAGUUGGAGAAUCAGCGUGUCCUGAAGGAACAGGCCCUGCAGGAGGCCAUGGAGCAGCUGGAGCAGCUUGAGUUAGAACGGAAGCAAGCACUUGAGCAGUACGAGGAAGUUAAAAAGAAGCUGGAGAUGGCAACUAAUAAGACCAAGAGCUGGAAGGACAAAGUGGCCCAUCAUGAAGGAUUAAUUCGACUGAUAGAACCAGGUUCAAAGAACCCUCACCUGAUCACUAACUGGGGACCUGCAGCUUUCACUGAGGCAGAACUUGAAGAGAGAGAGAAGAACUGGAAAGAGAAAAAGACCACGGAGUGACUGAGCUUGCUGGCAGUCACGUCAGUUAUGUAGAUACUGCAUGGCAGGAGAGCUUUACGCUAAAGACAAAAGAAACAGCUUUGGGGGCCGGGCGUGGUGGCUCACGCCUGUAAUCCCAGCACUUUGGGAGGCCGAGGCGGGUGGAUCACCUGAGGUCAGGAGUUCAAGAGCAGCCUGGCCAACCUGGUGAAACCCUGUCUCUACUAAAAAUACAAAAAAAAUUAGCUGAGCGUGGUGGCGGGCGCCUGUAAUCCCAGCUACUUGGGAGGCUGAGGCAGGAGAAUCACUUGAACGUGGGAGGCGGAGGUUGCAGCGAGCUGAGAUCAUGCCGUUGUACUCCAGCUUGGGCAACAGAGUGAGACUCCAUCUCAAAACAAAACAAAACAAAACAAAACAAAAAAACCCGGCUUUGCUGCUUUUAACUCUUCUUCCUUCUGUGCCUCUCUAAGUGGGUCAGUAUCCUAAGGAAGCCUUCUUAUUUAUCUUCCUGCAAACAAGGGUUACCUGAAAAGAAAAAAAAAGUCAACAUUGUCAAGCUGUUUGUUUACUCUUUCUUUGAAAACAUCACCUUCUGAAAUUUGUCUUUUAGCUCUCUCAGAUUCUUCCCCAAAUGAGGCAGGGUGCAGACAGCACAGUCAGCUCUGCAGAGUUUGGAGGGGCUCACUGCCACUGGGUACUCAGAACCUCUGUGGACUGGAUGUCAGCUCUUUCCUUUGGCAGCGUGUUUCCUUUUCCGAGUAUGUGCUGUUAAACUAGAUUGGCCGGUUCGCUUUCCAUUUCCUGACACUUGACAUGGAAUGCCUUUGACCAUUGGUGCUCUGACAGAGAAGUCAUGGAGUCAUUGCCAUUUCCUGGUUGCCCUUUUGGAAUGUGAUCCUGUUAGUAGAGGUUUUCUAGCUUCUACUAAGAUAUUUCUUUCCCUAACCAUCAUACACUUGGCAUGUUUCAUUCCCAUCUCCUUUCCCCUCACCUUAAAGGAGACUACCCCUUUGCCCCAUAUUGUCAACCUAAUUUUCUCUCGUACUCUCUCUAGUGAAUGAUGUGCUACCAAGUAUAUGCCAGGCUGUGAGAGGAUUAUACUGAGUAGUAGAAAGAAGCUAAUUUGAAAUAAAAAUUAUUUGUAUAAUUAAGAAAGCAGAUUAGAUGCACAUGGUCAACAGGAAGUUGACUGUAUGUCUGCUAGUUAGAUUCAAAACAUCAUAAAGAUGAUAGCAUGUCAAUAUAUUAGCCUAGCCAUUAUGUUAGCCUUUGUUAGGUGGGCAGCUUUUCUGCUUUUUCCCUUCCUCUGUGGUGACAACGGAGGAAAUAUCCAACAGAAAUACGUCUAACAGGGAAAUUGGGAUCAUAGUUUAUAUGCAUCUGAUUUGAAAGGAGUAUUGAGGAAGGUUUUCAUAUAUGAUCUAUCUUUGGAUUAAAAAGAACAUUUAUGAAAUCAAGCCUUCUAACACUAGUUAUAAUUGAGAAGCAACAGUAACUCCGUGGACAGCAAUCAAGCUUAAAAUUGUAAAUAAAUAUGGGGAUAAUUCAGUUGUUGCAAAAAAAGGGCAGAAUUCAGUAGAAUAAAGUCCUUUUCUCUUACAGGUAUUAAAUGAGGACAGAGAACCUCAGGUGUUCUUAUGCUAGUGCUUGCUGAGUGCAUACUAAGAAAGCAAUUCCAAAUAGAUGUAUACAUCUAGAGAGAGUGGUAUUAGAGAUUCAGUGUAUGUAUUUAUUUACAUGAGAGGAAACUGGAAUAUAAUCCCAUAAAUUAUCACCUUUUAUGACUGGAAAAUAUUUGCCAAUGAAGAAAUGGUCUGUAGGUAUUUGUCUUAAGAUUUUUGGCUGUUUAAUAAAAAUGUAACUUUAACGGUUUCUUAUAGUUGCCUUUAUAAAGUGUAUUGUCUAAAAUAUUUUUGUAUCAUGUGCCUUUGAAAUUUGACAGCUGAUUUGGGUGUUGGAUUUCUGCCCAGCCAUUUAUCAGUAUUAUCAUUUUAUUCAGUAGCUGGCAGGUGUAUUAGACCAACGAGACUUAGGUAAGGAAUGGAACCUUUCCUGUGGUUUGACUGCACAUUACACCAGAAGACUCCAGUAUCCCUCAUUCCAGAAUGAGGAAAAAGUAUUCUACAAAGAACCUAAUCACCUCUGUGAAAUCUAUGGGAUGGAAACAGUGUGGCCUUAGGAGUCAAAUAGUCUCUGCAUGGUGGGGAGGAUCAUGAUGGAAUAUGUGAAUUUCUACUUCUAGAAGUUGUGAAAUAGGUCCUGCACUUUUGCAGAAUGUCCUUCUUUAAACCUGGCUUAUUCCACAGCUGUAGCUGAUAACAUGACCUGGGGCUUAGCUGCUCUAGCCCUGGGUUCUUGGAGACCUCACACUGCCUGGCCCCUGGCCAUCCACCUAAGGACUGCCUGCUUUCUGGUCACAUGUGGACCUUGAUACGACUAAGCGGUUACAUAUGUGGUUGUGCAAAAGCUUUCUGUUUAAUGCAUAGUGUUACCGAUUUACAUCUUGGUUUUCAGUGGCACUAUGUCUAGGAGGCAAUAUCCUUUUAAACAGUGCUUUGGCUAAGAUAGAUACUUGUGAAUCAAAGAUAGCACAGAAAUGAACUAAGUAUAUCCCAUUUGGAAUUAUAUUUUGAUACUAUUUAAAAUGGUUUCACCUGUUAAAGGGCCAACAGAACUCUUGGUUUUACUUUUGUAAUUACUGUACAGAAAAUUUCAAGAGUGUUUGAGUGCUUGUCAUCAGGUGUUUUCCUUAAUAAGUAGGGAUAUGAUCAUUUACAGGAAUUAUAUAUGAAAAAAGUUUUUGAAAUGUAUUUUUGUGAUGUGCUAUGUUGAGGGGAAACCAAAUAUUUAUGAUUUUAAAACAUUCGUAUGAAAACAUUGUACAAUGUAAUAUGCUCAACUUUCUCAAUUUUUUGCUAAUUUUUCUAAGAUACAUUAAAAAUGUUUUAUAUUUUUUUUUAAGUAAAAUGGACCCAGUAAGAAAAUUAAAAAUACCAGAACAUACACUUUAAACUGUCUGAUUUAAUAAAACAGUGGGGGGUAAA